ACAGCUGUGUUUGGCUGCAGGGCCAAGAGCGCUGUCAAGAAGACCCACACGCCCCCCUCCAGCAGCUGAAUUCCUGCAGCUCAGCAGCCGCCGCCAGAGCAGGACGAACCGCCAAUCGCAAGGCACCUCUGAGAACUUCAGGAUGCAGAUGUCUCCAGCCCUCACCUGCCUAGUCCUGGGCCUGGCCCUUGUCUUUGGUGAAGGGUCUGCUGUGCACCAUCCCCCAUCCUACGUGGCCCACCUGGCCUCAGACUUCGGGGUGAGGGUGUUUCAGCAGGUGGCGCAGGCCUCCAAGGACCGCAACGUGGUUUUCUCACCCUAUGGGGUGGCCUCGGUGUUGGCCAUGCUCCAGCUGACAACAGGAGGAGAAACCCAGCAGCAGAUUCAAGCAGCUAUGGGAUUCAAGAUUGAUGACAAGGGCAUGGCCCCCGCCCUCCGGCAUCUGUACAAGGAGCUCAUGGGGCCAUGGAACAAGGAUGAGAUCAGCACCACAGACGCGAUCUUCGUCCAGCGGGAUCUGAAGCUGGUCCAGGGCUUCAUGCCCCACUUCUUCAGGCUGUUCCGGAGCACGGUCAAGCAAGUGGACUUUUCAGAGGUGGAGAGAGCCAGAUUCAUCAUCAAUGACUGGGUGAAGACACACACAAAAGGUAUGAUCAGCAACUUGCUUGGGAAAGGAGCCGUGGACCAGCUGACACGGCUGGUGCUGGUGAAUGCCCUCUACUUCAACGGCCAGUGGAAGACUCCCUUCCCCGACUCCAGCACCCACCGCCGCCUCUUCCACAAAUCAGACGGCAGCACUGUCUCUGUGCCCAUGAUGGCUCAGACCAACAAGUUCAACUAUACUGAGUUCACCACGCCCGAUGGCCAUUACUACGACAUCCUGGAACUGCCCUACCACGGGGACACCCUCAGCAUGUUCAUUGCUGCCCCUUAUGAAAAAGAGGUGCCUCUCUCUGCCCUCACCAACAUUCUGAGUGCCCAGCUCAUCAGCCACUGGAAAGGCAACAUGACCAGGCUGCCCCGCCUCCUGGUUCUGCCCAAGUUCUCCCUGGAGACUGAAGUCGACCUCAGGAAGCCCCUAGAGAACCUGGGAAUGACCGACAUGUUCAGACAGUUUCAGGCUGACUUCACGAGUCUUUCAGACCAAGAGCCUCUCCACGUCGCGCAGGCGCUGCAGAAAGUGAAGAUCGAGGUGAACGAGAGUGGCACGGUGGCCUCCUCAUCCACAGCUGUCAUAGUCUCAGCCCGCAUGGCCCCCGAGGAGAUCAUCAUGGACAGACCCUUCCUCUUUGUGGUCCGGCACAACCCCACAGACAGUGCCGGGUCCCCGCUCUGUGACUCAGGCAGCUGCGACUCCAGACAGCUCACUCAUCUGCCUAGAUCUCAGUCCUUCCACCCACAUCCAGCCUGAUGAGCUGUCCCACUCCUUCUGCUUCUCAACCCCCAUGGUUCUUCCACCCUCAGGAACAGUCCUUUUCAUGGGCCAAGUGAUGGAACCCUGACCCUGGGGAAAGACGCCUUCAUCUGGGACAAAACUGGAGAUGCAUCGGGAAAGAAGAAACUCCGAAGAAAAGAAUUUUAGUGUUAAUGACUCUUUCUGAAGGAAGAGAAGACAUUUGCCUUUUGUUAAAAGAUGGUAAACCAGAUCUGUCUCCAAGACCUUGGCCUCUCCUUGGAGGACCUUUAGGUCAAACUCCCUAGUCUCCACCUGAGACCCUGGGAGAGAAGUUUGAAGCACAACUCCCUUAAGGUCUCCAAACCAGACGGUGACGCCUGCGGGACCAUCUGGGGCACCUGCUUCCACCCGUCUCUCUGCCCACUCGGGUCUGCAGACCUGGUUCCCACUGAGGCCCUUUGCAGGAUGGAACUACGGGGCUUACAGGAGCUUUUGUGUGCCUGGUAGAAACUAUUUCUGUUCCAGUCACAUUGCCAUCACUCUUGUACUGCCUGCCACCGCGGAGGAGGCUGGUGACAGGCCAAAGGCCAGUGGAAGAAACACCCUUUCAUCUCAGAGUCCACUGUGGCACUGGCCACCCCUCCCCAGUACAGGGGUGCUGCAGGUGGCAGAGUGAAUGUCCCCCAUCAUGUGGCCCAACUCUCCUGGCCUGGCCAUCUCCCUCCCCAGAAACAGUGUGCAUGGGUUAUUUUGGAGUGUAGGUGACUUGUUUACUCAUUGAAGCAGAUUUCUGCUUCCUUUUAUUUUUAUAGGAAUAGAGGAAGAAAUGUCAGAUGCGUGCCCAGCUCUUCACCCCCCAAUCUCUUGGUGGGGAGGGGUGUACCUAAAUAUUUAUCAUAUCCUUGCCCUUGAGUGCUUGUUAGAGAGAAAGAGAACUACUAAGGAAAAUAAUAUUAUUUAAACUCGCUCCUAGUGUUUCUUUGUGGUCUGUGUCACCGUAUCUCAGGAAGUCCAGCCACUUGACUGGCACACACCCCUCCGGACAUCCAGCGUGACGGAGCCCACACUGCCACCUUGUGGCCGCCUGAGACCCUCGCGCCCCCCGCGCCCCUCUUUUUCCCCUUGAUGGAAAUUGACCAUACAAUUUCAUCCUCCUUCAGGGGAUCAAAAGGACGGAGUGGGGGGACAGAGACUCAGAUGAGGACAGAGUGGUUUCCAAUGUGUUCAAUAGAUUUAGGAGCAGAAAUGCAAGGGGCUGCAUGACCUACCAGGACAGAACUUUCCCCAAUUACAGGGUGACUCACAGCCGCAUUGGUGACUCACUUCAAUGUGUCAUUUCCGGCUGCUGUGUGUGAGCAGUGGACACGUGAGGGGGGGGUGGGUGAGAGAGACAGGCAGCUCGGAUUCAACUACCUUAGAUAAUAUUUCUGAAAACCUACCAGCCAGAGGGUAGGGCACAAAGAUGGAUGUAAUGCACUUUGGGAGGCCAAGGCGGGAGGAUUGCUUGAGCCCAGGAGUUCAAGACCAGCCUGGGCAACAUACCAAGACCCCCGUCUCUUUAAAAAUAUAUAUAUUUUAAAUAUACUUAAAUAUAUAUUUCUAAUAUCUUUAAAUAUAUAUAUAUAUUUUAAAGACCAAUUUAUGGGAGAAUUGCACACAGAUGUGAAAUGAAUGUAAUCUAAUAGAAGCCUAAUCAGCCCACCAUGUUCUCCACUGAAAAAUCCUCUUUCUUUGGGGUUUUUCUUUCUUUCUUUUUUGAUUUUGCACUGGACGGUGACGUCAGCCAUGUACAGGAUCCACAGGGGUGGUGUCAAAUGCUAUUGAAAUUGUGUUGAAUUGUAUGCUUUUUCACUUUUGAUAAAUAAACAUGUAAAAAUGUUUCAAAAAAAUAAUAAAAUAAAUAAAUACGAA